AGAGCCUUCCUGAUGUAUAUAUGCAGGUAGUGAGAAUUGAAUCGGCCCUUUGAGACAGUAAUAUAAUAAAACUCUGAUUUGGGGAGCAGCGGUUCUCCUUAUUUUUCUACUCUCUUGUGGGAAUGAGUUGCCAAGCUUUUACUUCGGCUGAUACCUUUAUACCUCUGAAUUCUGACGCCUCUGCAACUCUGCCUCUGAUAAUGCAUCACAGUGCUGCCGAGUGUCUACCAGUCUCCAACCAUGCCACCAAUGUGAUGUCUACAGUCCCAUCUAUUUUGUCUUUGAUCCAAACUCCUAAAUGUUUGUGCACACAUUUCUCGGUGACAACGUUGGGAAACACAGCAACAGGACUUCAUUAUUCUGUUCCUUCCUGUCAUUAUGGAAACCAGCCAUCAACCUAUGGAGUGAUGGCAGGUAGUUUAACCCCUUGUCUUUAUAAAUUUCCUGACCACACCUUGAGUCAUGGAUUUCCUCCUAUACACCAGCCUCUUCUGGCAGAGGACCCCACAGCUGCUGAUUUCAAGCAGGAACUCAGGCGGAAAAGUAAAUUGGUGGAAGAGCCAAUAGACAUGGAUUCUCCAGAAAUCAGAGAACUUGAAAAGUUUGCCAAUGAAUUUAAAGUGAGACGAAUUAAAUUAGGAUACACCCAGACAAAUGUUGGGGAGGCCCUGGCAGCUGUGCAUGGCUCUGAAUUCAGUCAAACAACAAUCUGCCGAUUUGAAAAUCUGCAGCUCAGCUUUAAAAAUGCAUGCAAACUGAAAGCAAUAUUAUCCAAAUGGCUGGAGGAAGCUGAGCAAGUAGGAGCUUUGUACAAUGAAAAAGUGGGAGCAAAUGAAAGGAAAAGAAAACGAAGAACAACUAUAAGCAUUGCUGCUAAAGAUGCUCUGGAGAGACACUUUGGAGAACAGAAUAAACCUUCUUCUCAAGAGAUCAUGAGGAUGGCUGAAGAACUGAAUCUGGAGAAAGAAGUAGUAAGAGUUUGGUUUUGCAACCGGAGGCAGAGAGAAAAACGGGUGAAAACAAGUCUGAAUCAGAGUUUAUUUUCUAUUUCUAAGGAACAUCUUGAGUGCAGAUAAGAUUUUUCUAUUGUAUAAUAGCCUUUUUCUCCCGUUUCAUUCCUUUCUCUUCCUCAACAAAAACAGAAAUUACUUGGUUGACUUAAAAUCAUUUUAUAUCAAUAGCUUUUACAGAAGCUUUACUUUUCCACUUUUUUUUAAAAAAAAGAAACCAACAAUUUAAAUUAUAUUGAUGUUAUUUACUUAAAAUAAUUAUUCUCAGAAGCCACAUUAUCUAUUUUAAGCCAAAUAUAUUAACAGUAAUAAAAUGAUCUCUCUGUCUCUCCCGCUCUCUUUCUCACACACACGCAGACAUAUGAGUAUGGGUUUAUAAGUUCCUUUUCCAAACAUGUAUAUUAGCUUUUUAACAUGUAAGUCAGUAAUGACACAUAUGUAAAGCACAUCACCAGAAAUAUCCAAUUCAAAAAUUAACCAAUGUUCUGCUUUCUACCAACUCUACUAAUUUGUCUGAACUAAAAGUUUUGAACUUAAGAGCUGGAGGUGUCUUAUA